UUAUCUAUGGCUGGGCUGGAGGAGGAGAGGUGAGCAGAAGUGGAGAGAGGCGGGGAGAGCAAGGGGAUGCCAAGAUUAUGGUGGGGAGGAGUUGGUGAAUGGACAGCAGCCAGGACAACAGCCAACCAUGAAAAGAAGUGUUCAUUAGCAGCCAGAUCCCACCCAGGUGCUGUGAGCACCCCUGCAAUCUCUCUUAACCUCCACUUUGGAAGACAGACAAUUAGGCUGUUUUUGUUCACAUGGCAGAGACUGCUUAUGGGAUACUCAGCUUUUCUAACAGUACAGGCCCUUUGUGGGAGGGUCAUGAAAGGUUUGGAGUGUGUUUGUUAUUCAGUACAAUGGGAUCAGUUAUGCUGCUGAAGGAAUCUUGUGGAAAUGUUUUUUUCUCUGCAGUGAGAAUAAGGAGGAGCAGGAAACACAGCAUAAUUAGCAUCAUCAUUAUUCUGGCUGGAGCAAUUGCACUCAUCAUUGGCUUUGGUAUUUCAGGGAGACACUCCAUCACAGUCACUACUGUCGCCUCAGCUGGGAACAUUGGGGAGGAUGGAAUCCUGAGCUGCACUUUUGAACCUGACAUCAAACUUUCUGAUAUCGUGAUACAAUGGCUGAAGGAAGGUGUUUUAGGCUUGGUCCAUGAGUUCAAAGAAGGCAAAGAUGAGCUGUCGGAGCAGGAUGAAAUGUUCAGAGGCCGGACAGCAGUGUUUGCUGAUCAAGUGAUAGUUGGCAAUGCCUCUUUGCGGCUGAAAAACGUGCAACUCACAGAUGCUGGCACCUACAAAUGUUAUAUCAUCACUUCUAAAGGCAAGGGGAAUGCUAACCUUGAGUAUAAAACUGGAGCCUUCAGCAUGCCGGAAGUGAAUGUGGACUAUAAUGCCAGCUCAGAGACCUUGCGGUGUGAGGCUCCCCGAUGGUUCCCCCAGCCCACAGUGGUCUGGGCAUCCCAAGUUGACCAGGGAGCCAACUUCUCGGAAGUCUCCAAUACCAGCUUUGAGCUGAACUCUGAGAAUGUGACCAUGAAGGUUGUGUCUGUGCUCUACAAUGUUACGAUCAACAACACAUACUCCUGUAUGAUUGAAAAUGACAUUGCCAAAGCAACAGGGGAUAUCAAAGUGACAGAAUCGGAGAUCAAAAGGCGGAGUCACCUACAGCUGCUAAACUCAAAGGCUUCUCUGUGUGUCUCUUCUUUCUUUGCCAUCAGCUGGGCACUUCUGCCUCUCAGCCCUUACCUGAUGCUAAAAUAAUGUGCCUCGGCCACAAAAAAGCAUGCAAAGUCAUUGUUACAACAGGGAUCUACAGAACUAUUUCACCACCAGAUAUGACCUAGUUUUAUAUUUCUGGGAGGAAAUGAAUUCAUAUCUAGAAGUCUGGAGUGAGCAAACAAGAGCAAGAAACAAAAAGAAGCCAAAAGCAGAAGGCUCCAAUAUGAACAAGAUAAAUCUAUCUUCAAAGACAUAUUAGAAGUUGGGAAAAUAAUUCAUGUGAACUAGACAAGUGUGUUAAGAGUGAUAAGUAAAAUGCACGUGGAGACAAGUGCAUCCCCAGAUCUCAGGGACCUCCCCCUGCCUGUCACCUGGGGAGUGAGAGGACAGGAUAGUGCAUGUUCUUUGUCUCUGAAUUUUUAGUUAUAUGUGCUGUAAUGUUGCUCUGAGGAAGCCCCUGGAAAGUCUAUCCCAACAUAUCCACAUCUUAUAUUCCACAAAUUAAGCUGUAGUAUGUACCCUAAGACGCUGCUAAUUGACUGCCACUUCGCAACUCAGGGGCGGCUGCAUUUUAGUAAUGGGUCAAAUGAUUCACUUUUUAUGAUGCUUCCAAAGGUGCCUUGGCUUCUCUUCCCAACUGACAAAUGCCAAAGUUGAGAAAAAUGAUCAUAAUUUUAGCAUAAACAGAGCAGUCGGCGACACCGAUUUUAUAAAUAAACUGAGCACCUUCUUUUUAAACAAACAAAUGCGGGUUUAUUUCUCAGAUGAUGUUCAUCCGUGAAUGGUCCAGGGAAGGACCUUUCACCUUGUCUAUAUGGCAUUAUGUCAUCACAAGCUCUGAGGCUUCUCCUUUCCAUCCUGCGUGGACAGCUAAGACCUCAGUUUUCAAUAGCAUCUAGAGCAGUGGGACUCAGCUGGGGUGAUUUCGCCCCCCAUCUCCGGGGGAAUGUCUGAAGACAAUUUUGGUUACCUCAAUGAGGGAGUGGAGGAGGAUACAGUGCUACUACCAACUAGUGGAUAGAGGCCAGGGAUGCUGCUCAACCUCCUACCAUGUACAGGACGUCUCCCCAUUACAACUACCCAAUCCGAAGUGUCAACUGUGUCAGGGCUAAGAAACCCUGGUUUUGAGUAGAAAAGGGCCUGGAAAGAGGGGAGCCAACAAAUCUGUCUGCUUCCUCACAUUAGUCAUUGGCAAAUAAGCAUUCUGUCUCUUUGGCUGCUGCCUCAGCACAGAGAGCCAGAACUCUAUCGGGCACCAGGAUAACAUCUCUCAGUGAACAGAGUUGACAAGGCCUAUGGGAAAUGCCUGAUGGGAUUAUCUUCAGCUUGUUGAGCUUCUAAGUUUCUUUCCCUUCAUUCUACCCUGCAAGCCAAGUUCUGUAAGAGAAAUGCCUGAGUUCUAGCUCAGGUUUUCUUACUCUGAAUUUAGAUCUCCAGACCCUGCCUGGCCACAAUUCAAAUUAAGGCAACAAACAUAUACCUUCCAUGAAGCACACACAGACUUUUGAAAGCAAGGACAAUGACUGCUUGAAUUGAGGCCUUGAGGAAUGAAGCUUUGAAGGAAAAGAAUACUUUGUUUCCAGCCCCCUUCCCACACUCUUCAUGUGUUAACCACUGCCUUCCUGGACCUUGGAGCCACGGUGACUGUAUUACAUGUUGUUAUAGAAAACUGAUUUUAGAGUUCUGAUCGUUCAAGAGAAUGAUUAAAUAUACAUUUCCUACACCA